GCAGUUGUCUUUGGUAGUUUUUUUGCACUAACUUCAGGAACCAGCUCAUGAUCUCAGGAUGUAUGGAAAAAUAAUCUUUGUAUUACUAUUGUCAGAUGGAGCCAACCCUGAAAAUUCUGGGAGAAGAGGACAGAAGGCAGAGGGAAGAGCAAGAGCAAAAAUUCUGAAACAGGAGAAAUUGUGAGCAUAUCAGCAUUAAGUACCACUGAGGUGGCAAUGCACACUUCAACCUCUUCUUCAGUCACAAAGAGUUACAUCUCAUCACAGACAAAUGGAGAAACGGGACAACUUGUCCAUCGUUUCACUGUACCAGCUCCUGUAGUGAUAAUACUCAUUAUUUUGUGUGUGAUGGCUGGUAUUAUUGGAACGAUCCUCUUAAUUUCUUACAGUAUUCGCCGACUGAUAAAGGCAUGAGGAUGUGGCCUGCAUGCUGCCUGAUCUUGCCUAGAACCGGCUGCACCUGCUGUUCUCUUGUUUAUGCAAACUGGCUGCACCUGCUAUUCCUUUGCUUAUGCCCCUACCCCUGGCUAUCCUAAUUCCCUGUUCUCCUGCCUCACUAUUACUGUAUUCUCUACUUCUAAAUAAAAAUAAAACAAAAUACAAACCGUU